CCUGUGCAGUGCGGGGGCUGCUGGCAGGCAGAGUGCCGCCCCAGGGGCCCUGGGAGCUGCAGGGCAUAUUGCUGCUGAGCCAGAAUGAGCUGUACCGCCAGAUCCUGCUGCUGAUGCACCUGCUGCCGCAAGACCUGCUGCUGCUAAAGCCCUGCCAGUCUUCCUACUGCUACUGUCAGGAGGUGCUGGACAGGCUCAUCCAAUGCGGGCUCCUGGUUGCUGAGGAGAACAAUGGCUCCGGGCGGCCAGCCUGUGACACAGGGCAACGGCGACUGAGCAGAAAGCUGCUGUGGAAACCGAGUGGGGAUUUUACUGAUAGUGACAGUGAUGACUUCAAAGAGACCGAGGGCCACUCAGCCAGCAGUCACACUGCCCAGAUUUCUUUCUUUUCCUCUGCCGCCUGCUCAGCCCGCUGCUCAAGGCCUUUGCACAGGCUGCCGCCUUCCUCCGCCAGGGCCAGCUGCCCGAUACUGAGUCGGGCUACACAGACCAGCUGUUCCAGUUCCUGCAGGCCACCGCCCAGGAAGAAGGGAUCUUCGAGUGUGCGGACCCAAAGCUUGCCAUCAGUGCUAUCUGGACCUUCAGAGACCUAGGGGUUCUGCAGCAGACGCCGAGCCCUGCAGGCCCCAGGCUCCACCUAUCCCCUACUUUUGCCAGCCAGGACAAUCAGGAAAAACUAGAACAGUUCAUCCGGCAGUUCAUUUGUAGCUAGAACUGUGAGGAGGAGCCUGUGCUGAGACUUCUCAGCCCCAGAACACAGCUGUGUCCUAGAGCCAGAAGAUGGAGAGGAGGCUGCAAACCCUUAGCUGCUCUAUAAAUAUAAUCAUUGAGGCUUGAUUGUCCCUUGCCAUCUCUUGCUUUUUCCCUCCUUUGAUGUGAUAAACAAGGGGACGAGACGAGUUGUCUUUUCCCCAGCCCAGCAGCA